GUUUGUUUUCCUGCCGGAGGCUGGAAAACGGCCGGGUUCCUGCUGCACUACCAUGCGCCGUGCGGCCCGUGCGACUCGCCGGACCUCGCGGGCGUCCCUGUACGGAGCCCUCGGCCGGUCCUAGCAGGGAUUGUCCCCAUUUCCAGCUCCGGAGCGGGCGGCUGCGCCCCGCUCGUCGAGGAGCUGCGCUCACCUCAGGGGCGGGCCCCCGCCUGCGUUCGCGGCGCCAGUAAGUGGGGCUCCGGGAUUUAGGGGCUUCUGCCGGGCGACCUGUCACUGUAGUAGCUGCUGGGAUGGGGCGGCGGGGAGACCCCUGGCCGUGGCCCCGCGACGGAUCGGAGGCGCAGGAAGAGGCUAAUGGGUUAUAGUUUCUUUCCGCGAUCCUGUGGAUCUCUCCUUCCUGGUAUGAAAACUCGGAGCCUGGAGGAUUUUGACGGGUGUUUAUCUUUUAGUCUUAAGGAGGGGGAAGACCCUAGCUAAUUUGAAGCCUCGUUGCGGGGCACGUUGAGGACUUGCUUUCGGAAUUUCCCUGACUAGGCCCUUGGCUGUCCCACAAGGGGUCUGAGCAAAAAUCCUCGAGUACUUAUUUGCAACCAUUUUUUACUGGAUUUCUUUCUGUUCUGAUUUCUUUCUUACUAAUCUGAGUAGCUGUUAUGAGAAGGAUAUUGACGGAUAUUCCAGAACAACUGAUUCUUUUGUAAUGUUAACCUUUUAAAGUUUGACUUUGACACUAACAUUAAGGACUUAUAUGUAAUAUAGCUAAUGCAUCAUUCUGCAGAGAAGAGUAUUCCUUUCCACUUACAACUAAAUAAGACCUGCUUUUGCUGGAGCUGUGCUAGGCUGAGGGAAUUCCACACUGAAUUUUACAAGCGGGAUGGAUUUCUCUAAGGAAGAUGACAUACAACGAUGGUUUGGGAGUCUUAAUUUGUUGGAAAGUGAAAUAAUGAAUGAUGGAGGAUUCAUACACAGAUGUGUCUCAACUUAGAGUGGGGUUACAUCCCUAUAAACCCAUUGCAGAAGACUGAUUUUUGGAAAUAUGUAUUUGGGAGACAGUCACGUCCUAUUGAAUACCUUGUGCUGGUGCUGCCAUCGAAAAAUCUGGUUACACUCUGGGGAGGACUGCUACCACUGCAGAACUGAACCACUUCGGCCGUGAGAUGAGUGUCCGGCCUGAGCAGGCACACCAUGAAUAGAUACACAACAAUCAGGCAGCUCGGGGAUGGAACCUACGGUUCCGUCCUGCUGGGAAGAAGCAUUGAGUCUGGGGAGCUGAUCGCUAUUAAAAAAAUGAAAAGAAAAUUUUAUUCCUGGGAGGAAUGCAUGAACCUUCGGGAGGUUAAGUCUUUAAAGAAGCUCAACCAUGCCAAUGUAGUCAAAUUAAAAGAAGUUAUCAGGGAAAAUGAUCAUCUUUAUUUUAUCUUCGAGUACAUGAAGGAAAAUCUUUACCAGCUCAUUAAAGAGAGAAAUAAGUUGUUUCCUGAGUCUGCUAUAAGGAAUAUCAUGUAUCAGAUAUUACAAGGACUCGCAUUUAUUCACAAACACGGCUUCUUUCAUCGAGACUUAAAGCCUGAGAACCUCCUCUGCAUGGGACCAGAACUUGUGAAAAUUGCAGACUUUGGUUUGGCCCGAGAAAUACGAUCAAAACCUCCAUAUACAGAUUAUGUAUCUACCAGAUGGUACAGGGCUCCAGAAGUACUCCUGAGGUCUACCAACUACAGCUCCCCCAUUGACGUCUGGGCGGUGGGCUGCAUCAUGGCAGAAGUUUACACCCUCAGGCCACUCUUCCCUGGAGCCAGUGAAAUUGACACAAUAUUCAAAAUUUGCCAAGUGCUGGGGACACCAAAAAAGACUGACUGGCCUGAAGGCUAUCAACUUUCAAGUGCAAUGAACUUCCGUUGGCCACAGUGUGUACCCAAUAACUUAAAGACCUUGAUUCCCAAUGCUAGCAGUGAAGCAGUCCAGCUCCUGAGAGACAUGCUUCAGUGGGAUCCCAAGAAACGACCAACAGCUAGUCAGGCACUUCGAUAUCCUUACUUCCAAGUUGGACACCCACUAGGCAGCACCACACAAAACCUUCAGGAUUCAGAAAAACCACAGAAAGGCAUCCUGGAAAAGGCAGGCCCACCUCCUUAUAUUAAGCCAGUCCCACCUGCCCAGCCACCAGCCAAGCCACACACACGAAUUUCUUCACGACAGCAUCAAGCCAGCCAGCCCCCUCUGCAUCUCACGUACCCCUACAAAGCAGAGGUCUCCAGGACAGAUCACCCAAGCCAUCUCCAGGAGGACAAGCCAAGCCCGUUGCUUUUCCCAUCCCUCCACAACAAGCAUCCACAGUCGAAAAUCACAGCUGGCCUGGAGCACAAAAAUGGUGAGAUAAAGCCAAAGAGUAGGAGAAGGUGGGGUCUUAUUUCCAGGUCAACAAAGGAUUCAGAUGAUUGGGCUGACUUGGAUGACUUGGAUUUCAGUCCAUCCCUCAGCAGGAUUGACCUGAAAAACAAGAAAAGACAGAGUGAUGACACUCUCUGCAGGUUUGAGAGUGUUUUGGACCUGAAGCCCUCUGAGCCUGUGGGCACAGGAAACAGUGCCCCCACCCAGACGUCAUAUCAGCGGCGAGACACGCCCACCCUGAGAUCUGCAGCCAAGCAGCACUAUUUGAAGCACUCUCGAUACUUGCCUGGGAUCAGUAUAAGAAAUGGCAUACUCUCGAAUCCAGGCAAGGAAUUUAUUCCACCUAAUCCAUGGUCUAGUUCUGGCUUGUCUGGAAAAUCUUCAGGGACAAUGUCAGUAAUCAGCAAAGUAAAUUCAGUUGGUUCCAGCUCUACAAGUUCUAGUGGACUGACUGGAAACUAUGUCCCUUCCUUUCUGAAAAAAGAAAUCGGUUCUGCUAUGCAGAGGGUACACCUAGCACCUAUUCCAGACCCUUCCCCUGGUUAUUCCUCCCUGAAGGCCAUGAGACCUCAUCCUGGGCGACCAUUCUUCCACACCCAGCCUAGAAGCACUCCUGGGUUGAUACCACGGCCUCCAGCCGCCCAGCCAGUGCAUGGCCGGACAGACUGGGCUUCCAAGUACGCAUCUCGGCGAUGACUGUCUGCCUUGGUGAUGAAUCUCUUCCUAGGGAGAAGCAGGAUACUUUCCCUCAGCUGACUGGUGUUCUACCUGCAAGAUGUGCAGAGGGCAUAAAAGCAAAUCAACACUUUAUAGUUAUUCUUCUGAACUAAGACAUGUCAAUAUUCUUUUUUAAAGUUUUUUUUUAAAAUAUUGAUUUGAAUGCAGUAGGCUUUUUUGUAUAAAAUUAUUUUAUUCUAAAACUGGGUCCCAUUAUUUUCUUAAACAACAGCAUUUUGUAUAUAUGGAUUAUGUUUUAGCAUUUUAUACAGUCAACUUUGUAAUGAACUUUUUAAAAAUUAAUUGAUUUUCCUUUGGGGUUCCAGAUAAUAUUUUCUACAGAUUUUGAAAAAUGUAAUAAUAUUAAUGCAGUAUUGCAACAGGGGUGCAAUUUAAGGCUAUGUGAUAGAGGGUUAUUUACUCAGUGUGUGCAGAUAUUUAUGAAGUGGUGAAAUUUCAAGUGUGGCUCACUAGGUACUUCAGGCCUUCUUGGACUGUUGUUAGAAAAGUGAUCCUCUGCUUUUCUUAGUAGGUCAUUGGUUUGAUUUUUGGAUACCACUCUGCUGUUCUAAAAGGACUAUUAUAUUAUAUAAUUCACUUUGUUUUACUUUUGUUCCCCAGAUGAAAGAACUCUAAGUAAAUACAUUUUAAAAAAUUUUUCUGACACCCUUUAAUGUGGUUGCAGAUCUCAGAUGAAACCAAGCUUAAUUAUACUAUGCCAUUAUAUUCUAAUUUAUUCCAUUUUUGAAAUCAAGUUGUAUGUGUACCAAUAAAAGAGAUUUCUGCUUCAAAAGGCUCUCAACAUGAAGGUUAACACAGUCAAUCAAACUUACAUUCCUGCCAAGAUGCAUGGCCAAAAAACUAAGUAUCAAAGCAGCAGAAGGUUUUUGAUUAUAGUAACUGAGAUGGAAUUUUGUGCCUAGCUCAGUUCUCCAGAUCUGGCUAGGAGCAGUCAAUGACUAAUGUUCUGUCCUAGCCAAAUUCUCAGGACAAUUUGGGGAGCAGAAAGAGUUAUGGCAGAGGUUCCACUCAUCUACAAAGUCACAGUCACAUGCCACAUUUGAUCUCCUAACCCUGGUGUAGUUUCUUUCAAGAGUGAGAACUUUAUUUGUUGGGCAGAGGCUGUUCCAUUGAGAGGAAUGUUUACAGCAGUUUCAAAAAUGACAAAGUCAGUUUGGAGACAGAAAAAGACAAAAGGUCCAGUCUCAUCCAUCUCUAUAUGGUACAUUUGCCUCACUUAUGGUUGCCUUAAAGGCAAGAGGGAAGGUCACCAUCAGUGAACGCAAUGCAAUCUCAACAGUGUAUUGAUUCAUAUUCUCCUAGGGCUCAAACUACUCUCUAUUGGUUCCAGGAUAAUGACAAAUUGAACCAUAUGUAAGUAAUCUUUUAUUUUUUAUUUUUUUUUUGAGACAGAGUCUCACUCUGUCACCCAGGCUGGAGUGCAGUGGCGCGAUCUUAGCUCUCUGCAACCUCUGCCUCCCAGGUUCAAGCCUCCUGAGUAACUGGGACUACAGGCGCCCGCCACCACGCCCAGCUAAUUUUUUGUAUUUUUAGUAGAGACGGGGUUUCACUGUGUUAGCCAGGACGGCCUCGAUCUCCUGACCUCGUGAUCCACCCUCCUCCACCUCCCAAAGUACUGGGAUUACAGGCAUGAGCCACUGCACCCAGCCAAGUGAUCAUUUUUAUAGGUUAAAAUGAUAGGUGAAAUGAAUAUAGACACUUUCAUAUGGUUCAACCUAAUGACUUGGUAAAUUAUUGCCUUGGUGUAUUAAUAAUAUGUUGCAUUCUGAACAAAUAACCAUGGCUUCCAAAGGGCCCUAACCUAAAAUCGGAGAGUAAUUUAUGCUUUGGAGAAUUUGACUCAAAUAUAUACUUGACCAAGCACCAUGAUCCCUAGGGGCAUGAGAAAAGCACAUAAUGGAUGUGGAUGUGAUAGGUGGUCUUUUCCUGUUAACAAGCUGGCAGCAAAGCUUCAGAAAAUAUAUAUGCAAGCACAACUUGAAGCUGAAUUCAUUUCUGUAUUAUAUUCUCAACUCGUUAUCUAAAGCAUCAGAACAUGUGUUUUCAGAGAUGAGUCCUUUACUAUAAGGUUAAUAUUUAUUUUCAUUUUCUGUAUUAUAUAUGAAAAGUAAAUUAAUGUGAAACCUGGCCCAGCUUGCUGGAAAGCAGGUUUUAAAUUGUAAAUAUUCCUUAGAGGAGCAAAUGGAUUGUUUAAUACCAUAGUCUCAGUAAUCUAGCUUAUAUAAGGUCAUUACAUUUUUUAACUGAAAAACCUAGUUACCUGAUUAUUGCACAUUAUAAAAUUGUUUUUCUAAUACUUUAUAGGGCCCAACUUCAGAAAAUACUUCGCUUUUUUCUUUUUAUGCUUUCGUUUGUUUACCAGCAAGCAACUUCCCUGGGGAAGCCAAACACAUAUUCAUAAAAAAAAUCAAGUAGCUGAUGUGCAGUUGAGAAAACUAGAGGACUGAAAAAACAAAUUUUAACUAGCAAAUGCUGUGAAUUACUCUUCCUCCCCUUCUCUGAAAUGGGUAAAGGACAAAUUGUGUAAAAAAACCUAUGCACUAUAGAAGGGAAUAGUAACCAUUUCUUUUGUCUCUCUGUUUCUGUUCUGACUGAGAACCUGCAGCCAUUUCUUGUUACAUGAAAACAAAAUGCUACUUGUUACCUCUAUUUUUUGUUACUAUACAAUUAUGAAAUGUAAUGUAAGACACCAACAGAAAUGAUAUACCUGUAACUGUACCUAUCAGGACUAUACCUCAUUUACAGUCAGAAAGCUUACUGGGAUGUCAGGAAAUGAUACAGGGUUGGUUCUCAUUUCGUGCCGAAAUGAGACAGAAAUUCAGUGACGAAGGUGCGUUGUAGGGGUAUUGAUGUGCCCCAGGUAGUGCCAGCAGAGUAGGGAAAACUGCAUUUGCAUAAAAACUACUCUUGACAUGAUUGUUCAUUUUACAAAAAAAUUCCAUUAAUUACCAAGCCCUCACCCAGCCCAUGUGUGAUAGGAUUUAUGUAGGAAGAAACUUGAUUUUCAAAUAAUUUUUUAAAUGUAUCUCUUGCCUAAAGGACUAUAUACAUCUAAUAAAGUAACACUGUGUCAUCUUCUGGAGUUAUCAAAAAUUGUAUACAAUCAAGACAACACAAGAAUUAUUUUAUUUUUGAGUGCAAAUACAGGUACUGUUGGAGUUGAUGGGCACCAUGCUUUCUCAUGAAGUAGCAUUUCCCUACCAUCAAGCCAUUGUUUUGUGCCAUUCAGGAGAGGAAAAAAAGGAAUUUAUGCUGUACAUUUCAGUUCAGUGUAUGACCAAAAGCAAUAUGUUUAUAAGAAGAUGUUUGACAUACUAAUUAUUUUAUAUCAUUUAAACCAUACUGUAGCAACAUAAUAUAUGGAGCUAAUUUGUAGAAUUAUUUUUACGAUUUCCAAACAAAUGUACUGUACUGUUAUAUAAUUUAUUGUGAGGACCUUCUCAUGGAAGCCAUUAGGAAAACAAACUAGAGGUAAAUAUCACAUUAAUCUGUAUUAUCAAUUUCUCAUAGACACUGUGCUAAUGUGAAUUUUAAAUGACCUGCAUCAAGUCUUCUGAUCUCAGAUAACUCAGUACAGAUAGCAAUUAGUCAGCUGAUUUGAUUACAAUGGAGUAACCGACAAUAUAUUUAUUUAUAAAGCACAUAUUCAUAAUAACGAGAAGAAUUCAGAAAACCACUUAAGCAAGACCCUUCUGAAAUAAAAAAUGUUGCUUUUUAAAUAGUUUGUCCUAAGGUGUUUAAAACAUGUCAACCUUAUGUAAGGAAAAAUUUCCUGGUCCAAAUAAAGUUGAAGUUUAAGAAAAA